UCAUAAUAACCUUAUAUGAAAUAGGCCCGGCUAUCUUACACAUAGGAAACCCGAGGCACAGAGAGAUUAAGUUGCUCAAGGCCACACAGCCAAUUAAUAAAAGGAAAUGGUGUUUGUAUUUCAAAGUGGCAGCUGAAUUUUACCUGGAGAGUCUGUUUUGCUUGUAUUUUCUGAUUAUAUCUGCUCAGUAGGUUAAUUCCAAUACAGAGUGGAUUAAGGAAGAGCCUCUUUACAACUGUGACUCCCAAGGACUUGGGCAUCUAUUGCUAAAAAAGCCUUUUCUCAAUGCACAAUAGUUUUGGGAAAAGGGGGAACAAUGUGACCCUUGGGGUCACUGAACAGAAGUCAUAAUGAGUUCCCCCACGAUACUGAAAUCACCAGCCUGGUAAUUGAAAUACAUUUUCAUUUGCAGAUGUGAAAAGCACUGGGAAGCUUUUAAGUCGCAAUCAGUGUAAUUCUGAACUGGCAGCAUAAUUUUAAAAGGCCCCUGCCUGGAACCAGGACCUUACUAAUUUCUGUGACCAAGGUCUUGUUUUCUCAUCCUAUCUUUUGUUCUUUCCUGCCAUUGCUUCCUCUGAUGUCUGCUUUCAAAAUUCAAGAUUAUCAGGCUAUGAAUUACCACUUACUCUUGUCUUUGUCCACUGUCUUUCAGCCUUAGGGGCAGACAGGGGUGGAUCCCUGGGGGAAUAACCUCCCUUGCACACUAGUUGAACAGUCUUCACAUAAGUGGAACAAGCAAAGACAACUUUUUUGGCUUGGUUUUUUCUGCAGUUCAAAAUCCAUUUUAAAUUACUUGAAUCUAGUCUUCAUAUAAGUGGAACAAGCAGAGAUAACUUUCUUGGCUUGGUUUUUCUCCAGUUCAAAACCCAUUUUAAAUUACUAGAAUCUGCACGUUUUUAAAGUAGUGGAAGAGGGUGGGAUAAAAAGAAGGAUAAUUCUGAAGCUGCUUUUCAAUGACGGUACGUUUAGCCACCUGAUUUCCUGAAACUGUGAAGGAGCCACAACUGUACACAGAUUUAGAAGUUAGAUCAUCAAACUUGCGGGUUUUUUUUUUUUUUUUAAUAUUUUUUGGAGCCGCCUACUGGCAGCUGAAACUAACUGAAAAGGGCUGUUUUCUGAAGUUCGUAGACCCAUAGUUGAGACUGGGAGCCUAAAAGAGCAUGUAUAGGGAAAACAAGGAAUUGGAAUCAGAUGGAUUUUUGCCCUAAUGCUGACUCCACCCCAACCAACUCUGUCACUUUUGAACAAGUUAGUUAAUUCCUCAGCCUCGGUUUCCUCAUCAGUAAAAUGGGACAAAUAAGUACUUCAAGGCCCCGUUACAUACAAUAAGCAUUCUGUAAAUUGUAGCUCUAAUUAUUAAGUAGACAUUUUAUGGAUAAAGAAACUCAAAUGCAGCGAUGCUAAAUGACUUGUUGACAGUCUCACAACUGGCUUUGAAUGAACCGAGGUCUGCUAUUCUAAGUAGUAUACACUUAAUCCUUACACUGGCACUGUGAAGUAGGUAUUAUAACUAUCAUUCCCAUGUUAAGGAUGAGAAAACAGAGACACCAAGAUGUUAGUAAAUAUCCUGAAUUCACAUAGGUUGCAAGUAGCAGAGCCAAGAUUUCAAACUCCAGGGCCUGUCUUUUUUUUUUUUUUUUUUUUUUUUGAGACAGGGUCUUACUCUGUUGACCAGGCUGGAGUGUAGUGGUGGGAUCACAACUCACUGCAGCUUCAAACUCAUGGGCUCAAGCGAUCCUCCUACCUCAGCCUCCCUGGUAGCUGGGACUACAUGCACAUACCACCACACCCAGCUAAUUUAUUUUUUGUAGAGAUGGGGUCUUGCUUUGUUGCCCAGGCUGGUCUUGAACUCCUGGCUUAAAGUGAUCCUCCUGCCUUGGCAUCCCAAAGCACUGGGAUUAUAGACAUGAGCCACUGCGCCCAGCCUCAGAGCCAGUCUUUAAGUACCACAAUAUACUGCCUCUUGGUGGGCUGUCUUAAAAGUGACAAAAUAAAUUAUGCUAACAAGAUCUUCCAAAUUAGCAGUUCCUUUUCUAAGUGGUCAAACUAGAAUGCUCUUCCCCGUGAGUAUUAGACUCAGUCAGCCACCUUUCUCUGCCUACAAAGCAUCUCUACUCAUGUAAUAAUAUGAAAACCAUUGAUGAUAAAAUGUUAAGUAACAGUGAGAUACAAAACAGUGCAUUCACAAGACUAUAACUAUGAUAAAAAGAAGCCUUAUGUGUAGAAGAAAAAAAAAAACAGAAGAAAAGGCACCAAUGUGUUAAGUGGUGGGAACAAGGCAAUGGAAUAAUACUUAUUUUUCUUAUUUUCUAGACUUUUUAUAAUGUGGUUUUGUUCAGUUUAUAAUUGAAAAGACAUAAUUUAUUUUUUAAAGGGAGGGAUGGAGGUCUUUUGAGCCAAGCAGAACAAGGACAAAGCUGCCUUCUUGAAAUGCUAGGGCCCAGACACUUUGUUUCUUUUCUGUAUUGAGGGGUUCUUUUCUCUUGUCGGGGAAACUGCUGGACUGACGCUGGUUAAAGCUGUUCAAAGAACAACAGCGCUACUUCACCUAACCUUCUUUGCUUCACCUCUUUGCUGAAUUCCAGAACUGUAUUUGUAAGUUUGUCCUCUUAGGACACAUGCUUUCUCUGGAAUUUUUAUUUUCGUUCUAUGAUUGCCCUAGCAUUGUGAAUAUUAGUGGUGAUCUGGGGAGGAGAGGAGUCUAAAGCUCUACUUUUCCAUUUACCUCCAUGUAGAACCAGCCCAGUUGAGAGCCUCCAUCCCUGGGCAGGAGCCAAGGUCAACAGUAGCAGUGACUGGGCAGGGACAGUCUCUGGGUCAUCAGUAGGAGGGUACAAUGACUCUUCUUGCUUUUCACCUAAGUUGAAUAAGCACCCUGUGCACUUUAAUCUCCUGUCGGUACCAUUGGGCCAACUAAAGACAAGGUUUUGAAAUCUCAGCUAUAAAAGACAUCCAGCCAAACUCUCAGUCUUGCCUUAACAAUGUUCCAGAGGCUGAAUAAAAUGUUUGUGGGUGAAGUCAGUUCUUCCUCCAACCAAGAACCAGAAUUCAAUGAGAAAGAAGAUGAUGAAUGGAUUCUUGUUGACUUCAUAGAUACUUGCACUGGUUUCUCAGCAGAAGAAGAAGAAGAAGAGGAGGACAUCAGUGAAGAGUCACCUACUGAGCACCCUUCAGUCUUUUCCUGUUUACCGGCAUCUCUUGAGUGCUUGGCUGAUACAAGUGAUUCCUGCUUUCUCCAGUUUGAGUCAUGUCCAAUGGAGGAGAGCUGGUUUAUCACCCCACCCCCAUGUUUUACUGCAGGUGGAUUAACCACUAUCAAGGUGGAAACAAGUCCUAUGGAAAACCUUCUCAUUGAACAUCCCAGCAUGUCUGUCUAUGCUGUGCAUAACUCCUGCCCUGGUCUCAGUGAGGCCACCCGUGGGACUGAUGAAUUACAUAGCCCAAGUAGUCCCAGAGUGGAAGCUCAAAAUGAAAUGGGGCAGCAUAUUCAUUGUUAUGUUGCAGCUCUUGCUGCUCAUACAACUUUUCUGGAACAACCCAAGAGCUUUCGCCCUUCCCAGUGGAUAAAAGAACACAGUGAAAGACAGCCUCUUAACAGAAAUAGCCUUCGUCGCCAAAAUCUUACCAGGGAUUGCCACCCUCGGCAAGUCAAGCACAAUGGCUGGGUUGUUCAUCAGCCCUGCCCGCGUCAGUACAAUUACUAAUAGUUUCAAGUUUUGUUGGUUGGUUUCUCUUGGUUUGUGCUUACAUGUAUGGAUGUGUGUAUAUGUACAGUGAAAAUGUUGUCUCUUUACAACCAAUUGAUAACCAAUCACAUAGUUUUAUCAGUGUAUUUAGACACUAUCUUGAAAAUCAGAUUUAUAUGCUGUGUAUCACAUAAUGCCUUGCCUUUAACAUUUACUUUUUUUGUACACUUUUUCAGAUUAUUUCUGGAAACAUAUCAAUAUAAUUACAGUGUUUGGGGGUGUCUUUAAAUAUAUUAGGUUAUACAUUAGUCAGCAUUUUAAAGACAUUUCUUCCCAAGUACGAGAAUAGGCAUCUUUCAUUUUCAUUUUAUUUUGUAUUACUUAAUCUUUUAAGCAAGCAAAAAUUUAUUCUCAGGGUCAGCUGUACACUUUAUUGACCAGUACUUGAUAAUCUCUCUGUAUAUGAUGAAUACAUUUUUACACACUAACAUUAGCAUUAACAGGUGAUAGUUGCCAUGGAUAUAAUGGAAUUAUGGCUGGACUUUCUUUUGAAAGAAAACUUGAUGUAUUCUGUGUGUAUGGUUUUUCCCCAGAUUAGUCAUACAGUUCAUUUGGAAUUCAGGUACAUUAAGCUUUAGUGAAGAGUGCAUGCAGUAAUUCCAAUGUGACUGCAUGACGUGGUACAGACAUUACAGGUGUUGUAGACAGAGGCACUUGUCUCGUGCAGAGGGAUUAAAUUAGACCUGUGAGAUUAUAUUUGGAAAAAUUCAUGUCUGUAACUAACCCAUUAGUGCAGUAUUUAAUUUGUUACUAUUCCUUCCCGCCAAUUCUGUCCACUCCUCACCUCGCAUCAGCUAUAAAUUUGGAAGUACUUGUCCAGGCACUCAAGUGACUUCAUAUUUCUCUCUGCCCAUGGGAAAAGAGAUAGGCUUUAUAUUUCCACAGAGUGAAAAAUCCUCUGUCAUGGAGCCUGUCCUGCCAAGUGGCAAGAGUGUGGGGACUGUCUGGUGAUGAUGUCUUUCAUGGCAUCUGAGUGAAGAGUGACAGGUUGGCUCAACUUUUUUCUUUUUUUUUUUUUAAUUGCCUUGUAUUGUAAGUAUUCUUCCCUGCAGUCCAAGUGACUUUUCAUUUUUUGUUUUAACUUCAGGCAAAAUCUUUAACCACUCUGGCCUCUGUUUCCCCCACCAACGGGGAGCAGUGACAUUUACCUCCCUCACAGAGUCACUGUGAGGAUUCUAUACUGAUUUGAAGUGGAGCUGUUCAGAACUGAACCUUGUAGGAAAUUCCAAGGGCCUUUCUACUGAAUCUGGUGAUGGGGUGGGGCCGUGGCACUUUCUCUGCCACAGCUGUUCUUCACAGUGUUGGUGCUAAUGAGGCCAGGGUGCAGGGUUCGAUUCACACGUAGGCCAGUUAACUUAGAGAAAAUCUAUUUCCUUACCUCUAGCCAGUCACUUCCUUUUUCCGCAGUUGUGAUGGGUUUUGCUGAGCCAUCCACUCUGACUGAUUUCCUCUGAAGUAAACAUAUUUACAAUCCAAAGCAAUUCUACUGACAGAAGUGUUGCCUUCAUAAUCAAACAGCUUGUUUUUCCAUCUCCUCUGCAACCCUAAUUAAAUGAGUACAGGUCUACAAAAUGUUUUCAAGGAGAAAAGCAGCAUAUCCUUAAGUGAAGUAUUAUAUUUUUCAAUAACCCUGUAGUGGCUUGAUGCAGGGAACCCUGGGGGACUUUCAGCGAAGAGCUGUGCUCUUUUCUGACUAGAUUAGAGCGUUUGGAGUGGAAGACGUCAAAUGUGUAGUGAGAUGGAGGUUUUACAUUGUUCUUCUACUGGCUGUGAUGAAGUGCCAGAAUGUCUCUUUAGAACAAGAGUUAGAUUCCCCCUUUCUCCUUAUUGCCCCUUCCGUUUUGACUUCCCCUUUAUUUAUUUGUUGUCUAAUUAGGGGCCAAGUCUGUAAAGUUUUGUCAAAGUGAGUUAGAAGUUGUUUUCUCUUACUAUUUGUGUUUACCAGAGUUGGGAGAUAAGAUAGUUUCCAUGAAGGUGUGUAUGUUUUAUACGAUGUUUGUUAUAGGGCCAUGCAUUGGUAACUUGAAAAUAGACCAGCUUAAUGUCUUCAGGAUGUAAAACUCUGAAUACACGGCGUCUCUUUUUCAUACAUUGCAUGUAAGUUGUUAGUACCUCACAAGCUACAGAAGUUCAGCCAUGAGAUUUUGUUUGGCAACAUGAACAGAUUUGUGUAUAACUGCAAUGGCCUUUUUUUCCAGAUUUCCUUAUUGACUUUUUGUUUGCCUUACCUGGGGCUAGUUUUUUAUGCUUUGUACCUAGAAAACAAAAAAUUACAUUCGUUGGGCUUUUUUUCAAGGUUGGGAUUACCACACCACCUGGAAUAUCAUACUGUGGUUUCUGCCUAAAAUUGGCACAUGUAAGUAUUGAAGAAAAUGGUUAUAUAAUUCAGUUGAAACUCUUGGUUAUUAGAUGUUAGGCAUCUCCUGUAUGUAAGACACAAGGCCAACCACAACACAGAACGAUGUUGACCUGUUAAGUAUUCUCUGAAACAUGGCCAAAAUGCAUUUUAUGAGCUUUUUUUUUUGCUAUUGUAAAUAUUAGUGGUUUACAAUGCGCUUUAGACAUAUUUCUUUAAAAUGCAAGCAGUGAGAAAUAAGACCUCUCUGAAUUAGUAGCUCUAAACUGUUAACAUAGAAUGUUACUUGGAAAAAGUCUGGAAUAUGUGGUGUACACAAGCAGUGCUUCGUGAAUGAGUUUCUUAGCUUUUAUAGUGCGCCAUGUUUCUCAAAGUUUGUUUUUGUUGACAAAACAUUUUAUAAUAUAUAUCUUAUGUUUAUUUUUUUUCUCAACUAAUUGUGUACUGCACUGUAAGGUGAAAAUUAGCCAUCCAUUAUUUAUCUUCUGUGGCAAUGCAUUUAUAUGGUUGAUUGGGUGGGGAAUUUUUUGCAGAAAGAUGCAAAGUGAUUGGGUUUUCGACUUCCUAUCGCAGGGAGCUUUUAAGAAAUAUUAAUUUCCUAUACAUUUUUCCAAUCCCCAUGCAAACUGUUCCUGUUUACAUACCUUCUCUGUUGUAUCAGUACUUUGAGUGAGAAGACAGUUUAUUUAAAACUUGAGCAGGCUGUUCAGCAUUGUUUCUGCUUCUGAAAUCUGUAUAGUACACUGGUUUGUAAUCAUUAUGUCUUCAUUGAAAUCCUUGCUACUUCUCUUCCUCCUCAAUGAAAUACAUUAUAUAUUAUCUUUAUGUACUCUUAAGAAAAACGAGCAAGGAAGAGUAUCUUCAUUAUUCUCAUUUUCUCUGAGUUGGAAACAAAAACAUGAAGGACUCCAACUAGAAGACAGAUAUUUACAUUUAAAUAGAUUAGUGGGAAAACUUUAAGAGUUUCCACAUAUUAGUUUUCAUUUUUUGAGUCAAGAGACUGCUCCUUGUACUGGGAGACACUAGUAGUAUAUGUUUGUAAUGUUACUUUAAAAUUAUCUUUUUAUUUUAUAAGGCCCAUAAAUACUGGUUAAACUCUGUUAAAAGUGGGCCUUCUAUCUUGGAUGGUUUCACUGCCAUCAGCCAUGCUGAUAUAUUAGAAAUGGCAUCCCUAUCUACUUACUUUAAUGCUUAAAAUUAUACAUAAAAUGCUUUAUUUAGAAAACCUACAUGAUACAGUGGUGUCAGCCUUGCCAUGUAUCAGUUUCACUUGAAAUUUGAGACCAAUUAAAUUUCAACUGUUUAGGGUGGAGAAAGAGGUACUGGAAAACAUGCAGAUGAGGAUAUCUUUUAUGUGCAACAGUAUCCUUUGCAUGGGAGGAGAGUUACUCUUGAAAGGCAGGCAGCUUAAGUGGACAAUGUUUUGUAUAUAGUUGAGAAUUUUACGACACUUUUAAAAAUUGUGUAAUUGUUAAAUGUCCAGUUUUGCUCUGUUUUGCCUGAAGUUUUAGUAUUUGUUUUCUAGGUGGACCUCUGAAAACCAAACCAGUACCUGGGGAGGUUAGAUGUGUGUUUCAGGCUUGGAGUGUAUGAGUGGUUUUGCUUGUAUUUUCCUCCAGAGAUUUUGAACUUUAAUAAUUGCGUGUGUUUUUUUUUUUUUUAAGUGGCUUUGUUUUUUUUUCUCAAGUAAAAUUGUGAACAUAUUUCCUUUAUAGGGGCAGGGCAUGAGUUAGGGAGACUGAAGAGUAUUGUAGACUGUACAUGUGCCUUCUUAAUGUGUUUCUCGACACAUUUUUUUUCAGUAACUUGAAAAUUCAAAAGGGACAUUUGGUUAGGUUACUGUACAUCAAUCUAUGCAUAAAUGGCAGCUUGUUUUCUUGAGCCACGGUCUAAAUUUUGUUUUUAUAGAAAUUUUUUAUACUGAUUGGUUCAUAGAUGGUCAGUUUUGUACACAGACUGAACAAUACAGCACUUUGCCAAAAAUGAGUGUAGCAUUGUUUAAACAUUGUGUGUUAACACCUGUUCUUUGUAAUUGGGUUGUGGUGCAUUUUGCACUACCUGGAGUUACAGUUUUCAAUCUGUCAGUAAAUAAAGUGUCCUUUAACUUCA